GGAAAAAAGGAAAGUGCACUUGGAAGAGAUCCAAGUGGGCAACUUGAAGAACAAGUGCCAAAUAGCACUUCUGUCAUGCUGGAUGUCAGGGCUCUUUGUCCACUUUGUAUAGCCGCUGGCUUAUAGAAGGUGCUCGAUAAAUCUCUUGAAUUUAAAAAUCAAUUAGGAUGCCUCUAUAGUGAAAAAGAUACAGUAAAGAUGAGGGAUAAUCAAUUUAAAAAAUGAGUAAGUACACACAAAGCACUUUAUCCAUUCUUAUGACACCUGUUACUUUUUUGCUGUGUUUGUGUGUAUGCAUGCCAUGUUAUAGUUUGUGGGACCCUCAAAGCAAGCUGGGGAGAGUAUAUACUGAAUUUAGCUUCUGAGACAUGAUGCUCUUCCUUUUUAAUUAACCCAGAACUUAGCAGCUUAUCUAUUUCUCUAAUCUCAAAACAUCCUUAAACUGGGGGUGAUACUUGAGUGAGAGAAUUUUGCAGGUAUUAAAUGAACUAUCUUCUUUUUUUUUUUUCUUUGAGACAGAGUCUUGCUCUGUCACCCAGGCUGGAGUGCAGUGGCGUGAUCUCAGCUCACUGCAACCUCCGCCUCCCGGGUUCAAGUGAUUCUCCUGCCUCAGCCUCCUGAGUAGCUGGGAUUACAGGUGCGUGCCACCGUGCCCAGCUAAUUUUUGUGUUUUUAGUAGAGACGGGGUUUCACCAUGUUGGCCAUGCUGGUCUUGAACUCCUGACCUCGUGAUCUGCCCACCUCGGCCUCCCAAAGUGCUGGAAUUAUAGGCGUGAGCCACCGCGCCCAGCAAAGAACUUCUAACCUUCAUAACCUGACAGGUGUUCUCGAGGCCAGGGUCUCUCUUUCUGUCCUUUCACGAUGCUCUGCAUCCCUUGGAUGUGCCAGUUUCUGGGGGAAGAGUAGUCCUUUGUUACAUGCAUGAGUCAGUGAACAGGGAAUGGGUGAAUGACAUUUGUGGGUAGGUUAUUUCUAGAAGUUAGGUGGGCAGCUUGGAAGGCAGAGGCACUUCUACAGACUAUUCCUUGGGGCCACACGUAGGUUCUUGAAUCCCGAAUGGAAAGGGGAGAUUGAUAACUGGUGUGUUUAUGUUCUUACAAGUCUUCUGCCUUUUAAAAUCCAGUCCCAGGACAUCAAAGCUCUGCAGAAAGAACUCGAGCAAUUUGCCAAGCUCCUGAAGCAGAAGAGGAUCACCCUGGGAUAUACACAGGCCGAUGUGGGGCUCACCCUGGGGGUUCUAUUUGGUGGGUUCCCCUCUGCAGAUUCUGACCGCAUCUCCCCUCUAAGGAGUAUCCCUGAACCUAGUGGGGAGGGGCAGGGGCAGACUACCCUCACCCAUGAAGAGGAGUAGGGAGAGGGAGAAGAUGCUUUGAGCUCCCUCUGGGAAGAGGUGGUAAGCUUGGAUCUCAGGGUCACAAGGGCCCUGCGUGCUCCCUCACUUUGCUUCUCUUUUGACUGGCCUCCCCCAGGGAAGGUAUUCAGCCAAACGACCAUCUGCCGCUUUGAGGCUCUGCAGCUUAGCUUCAAGAACAUGUGUAAGCUGCGGCCCUUGCUGCAGAAGUGGGUGGAGGAAGCUGACAACAAUGAAAAUCUUCAGGAGAUAUGCAAAGCAGAAACCCUCGUGCAGGCCCGAAAGAGAAAGCGAACCAGUAUCGAGAACCGAGUGAGAGGCAACCUGGAGAAUUUGUUCCUGCAGUGCCCGAAACCCACACUGCAGCAGAUCAGCCACAUCGCCCAGCAGCUUGGGCUCGAGAAGGAUGUGGUCCGAGUGUGGUUCUGUAACCGGCGCCAGAAGGGCAAGCGAUCAAGCAGCGACUAUGCACAACGAGAGGAUUUUGAGGCUGCUGGGUCUCCUUUCUCAGGGGGACCAGUGUCCUUUCCUCUGGCCCCAGGGCCCCAUUUUGGUACCCCAGGCUAUGGGAGCCCUCACUUCACUGCACUGUACUCCUCGGUCCCUUUCCCUGAGGGGGAAGCCUUUCCCCCUGUCUCCGUCACCACUCUGGGCUCUCCCAUGCAUUCAAACUGAGGUGCCUGCCCUUCUAGGAAUGGGGGACAGGGGGAGGGGAGGAGCUAGGGAAAGAAAACCUGGAGUUUGUGCCAGGGUUUUUGGGAUUAAGUUCUUCAUUCACUAAGGAAGGAAUUGGGAACACAAAGGGUGGGGGCAGGGGAGUUUGGGGCAACUGGUUGGAGGGAAGGUGAAGUUCAAUGAUGCUCUUGAUUUUAAUCCCACAUCAUGUAUCACUUUUUUCUUAAAUAAAGAAGCCUGGGACACAGUAGAUAGACACACUUA